AUCCUACCCUGUGCCGCAGCCGCAUCGCCACCGCAGCCCGGCAGAGCCGAGCCCGGCCCAGGCCCCUGCCCCUGCCCGGCCCUCGGCCAGUCGCCCCCGGCCCCGCCCCCGCCCGCAGGCCCCCCGCAGCGGCCGCGGCGCCCCCCGGCGCCCCCAGACCCCGGCCUCCGGCACAGAGGCGGGAGACCCGGAGCAGCAGCAGAGGCAGGAGGACUAGGAGGAGGAGGAGGAGCCGUCGCAGGAUGAAGGAUCGGACUCAAGAGCUGCGGAGUGCGAAAGACAGUGAUGAUGAAGAGGAGGUGGUCCACGUGGAUCGGGACCACUUCAUGGAUGAGUUCUUUGAACAGGUGGAAGAGAUCCGGGGCUGCAUUGAGAAACUGUCGGAGGAUGUGGAGCAGGUGAAAAAACAGCAUAGCGCCAUCCUGGCCGCACCCAACCCAGAUGAGAAGACCAAACAGGAGCUGGAGGAUCUCACUGCAGACAUCAAGAAGACGGCCAACAAGGUUCGGUCCAAAUUGAAAGCGAUCGAGCAAAGCAUUGAACAGGAGGAGGGGCUGAACCGUUCCUCCGCGGACCUGCGCAUCCGCAAGACCCAGCACUCCACACUGUCCCGGAAGUUCGUGGAGGUAAUGACCGAAUAUAACGCGACCCAGUCCAAGUACCGGGACCGCUGCAAGGACCGGAUCCAGCGGCAACUGGAGAUCACUGGAAGGACCACCACCAACGAAGAACUGGAAGACAUGCUGGAGAGCGGGAAGCUGGCCAUCUUCACAGAUGACAUCAAAAUGGACUCACAGAUGACGAAGCAGGCGCUGAAUGAGAUUGAGACGAGGCACAAUGAGAUCAUCAAGCUGGAGACCAGCAUCCGCGAGCUGCACGAUAUGUUUGUGGACAUGGCCAUGCUCGUAGAGAGCCAGGGAGAGAUGAUUGACCGCAUCGAGUACAACGUGGAACAUUCUGUGGACUACGUGGAGCGAGCUGUGUCUGACACCAAGAAAGCAGUGAAAUAUCAGAGCAAGGCCCGGAGGAAGAAAAUCAUGAUCAUCAUUUGCUGUGUGGUGCUGGGGGUGGUCUUGGCGUCAUCCAUUGGGGGGACGCUGGGCUUGUAGGCCCCCCCCACCCUUCUCUCUCCCAGACCCUUCCCCCACCACAUCGGGAGCAAUACCCCCACCACCCCUUUCACUCCAUCCCCUGCUCCAGGCUCACUCCCAAAACAGACCCAGGCAGCCCCACCCCCACGGCAGACCCUGGUGUCCCUGGACCUCACCGGGCCAUGGACCCCCCCCCCGUCCCCGCACGUAGAUCGCAGCAGGCGUGAUUACACAUGCACACCAACAUGCAUGCCGCCGGCACAUGCUCGAGACGUGUGGACACCCCAGCGUGCGUGUGCGUGUGAUGUGUGUGAUGCACCAGAGCACCCCCUCCACCCCCACCUUGGGUGUGUGUGCGUGGUCUGAGCUUCCCCCUUCACCGGGGCUGUUGUGUAGACUGCAGCCAAGUGUAACACAGCAGUCCAUCACGCCCUCUCUGUCCUCUGUGAACAGUGUGUGUGCGUGCGUGAGACCACAGAUCUGUGGACACACCAUUUGUGUACGUGGAAUUUUGUGUUUCAGUGUUUGAACCUAAUGCAACAGCAACAAAGCCACUGAUACCUGAGCCCUUUGUGUCUGCUACAAACCAGGCAGGUGGUGUGUGUGGACUCACACUCACAUUCUCAGAGGAUCCAGGGAGGCCCAGGUACACACAGGCCAUGGCAGACACCCCAUGUCUUUGUUACCCCAGGGGCUGUGGCAUGUCCCAGGAGGGUGUGCAUGUGUGUGUGUGUGUGUGUGUGUGUGUCCAGGAUGUGCCUGAAGUAUUGAUAGGUCUUCUCAGAUAGAGCCCUCCACACUGUGGACUGGACACCUGUUUUGGGAGGGCACAGAAAUGUGUAUUUCUUGCUACCUAGAAUGCAGCUGUGUGUGUGUGGCGUGCGUGUGUAUGCACGUGUGUGUGUGUGUUAGGGGCUCUCUACAUGGUGUGCUUUUUAAUUUUUUUUUGUUUUUUGUUUUUUGUUUUUUUCGAGACGGAGUCUUGCUCUGUCACCCAGGCUGGAGUGCAGUGGCGCAAUCUCAGCUCACUGCAACCUGUGCCUCCCUGACGCAAGCGAUUCUCAUGCCUCAGCCUCCCAAGUAGCUGGGACUACAGGCGCCUGCCACCACGCCUGGCUAAUUUUAGAAUUUUAGUAGAGAUGAGGUUUUGACAUGUUGGCCAGGCUGGUCUCGAACUCCUGACCUCAGGUGAUCCGCCCACUUUGGCCUCCCUAAGUGCUGGCAUUACAGGCCUGAGCCACCACGCCUGGCCUACAUGAUGUGUUUCUGUCCUGCCUGACCUACAUGGUGUGUUUCUGCCCUGCGUAUUACACACACACACACACACGUGCGUGCACACACACUUCUAAGGACGUGGCCCCAUCUGGCUUUGUCUCUCCAGUUGUCCUUGCCCUGCCCCCCUCCCCAGAGGUGCUGCCCAGUGCUGGUGUGGCCACACACGGCUACAUCAUUGUGCAGGCAGAGCUCCCUGCCUGCCCAGCCUCAGGGCUCUGCAUGCUCACACCUAGAUCCUCAUCUUCCUCCAUGUCUCUGCCCAGCAUAGCCCCGAGCCCCUGGAAGCUGGUACCCCUCAGUGUGCUCACACGUGGCAAGGCCGAGGUGGCCCCAGGCAGGGGCCAUACCAGGCACAAACCAUGCACGCUGGCAUGGGUGCGGGGAUCACACGAAUGCCUCCUGGAAGGAAAGGGCUACUUGUAGGAAUGUUACUGAUGAGGCAAGAUGCCAAGGACUUCCCUGCAGGGAUCAAAGAUCAGGACACGACCCCUUCCUCACACACCCACCUCAGACCUGGGAGAGGACUGUGUGUCCCCCACUGCCCCAUCGGAUGCUCUGGGCUCUGCCUCAGGGAACUCGGGUUUGGGGAAAUGUCUAUUUCAGAAGUACUGGAGUGGCCAGUGUGGCAGUGGCCACUCAGGGUGGGCUGGGUCCUGAGACCCAUCCCCGACACCUCUCCUGCUGAACCCUCAGGCUGCUCCCCACACCAGGGUGUGACUGAGGGGUACACAGGCCUGGAUUUCUGGUGUGAGGAAGGGGCUAGCACCUCCCCUGUUGUGUAGCCAGCACAGGCACAAUUUGUGGGUUUGGUGGCAGGUAGGUGGUGCGUGGGAGAAAGGACAGUGUUAGAGGUCCCCACUCCGUGGUCUAGGAUCAUGAAAGGUGAACACACAAGUACACAAAUGUGCCAUGCCCUGGCAUGGGGCUUAUGUGUGCACAGGCAAGGCACUCGGUGUGUGUGUGCGGACCCCAGGGUCCCAGGUCAUGUGAAGCGUACGUGUGUGUGCAUUGUAUGUGUGUGUACAUUGUGUGUGCAUUGUGUGUGCAUGUGGCCAAACAGAUGUGACCUCCCAGAACACAGUACCCCUCCACCUCUACCCGAGCUCAGACAGCCGAGCUCUCCCUUGUCCUGUGUGUGUGUCAGUGUGGCCACGUGCGUAACCCCAGGUGGGCUGUCCUGAGCUGGGGGCCUGCCUGUCCCUUCCCAGAACGCCCCUCUGCAGGACAGGAAGUCUGCCCCAAGUCUGGCCACGGCCCUCCUGCUCCCAUCUCGGGCUGCUUGGGAGACAUCAGAGCAGGCCCCAGCCCCCAGUCCCCUCUUCCGGCCGCCUGGACAGGACCCCCAUUCAGCCCAGGUGUUUCCGGAAGUCCCACGGCCUUGGGGCCACAGGAGAAGGGUUGAAGCGUGGCUGGGGCACCACUCCCCCCACCUGGAGUGGCAUUGGGCCCACAGCUGCCCAUCUCUGGGCCUCAGGUGGACCAGGGGAUCUCUAAGGGUCUGCUGUGCCCUUUCUAUGCGUCCUCCACAUCCUAUGAUGUGCCUGCUUGUUGGCUGCUGUCUGUGUGCGUCCUGGCAUGUUGUCUGGAGGCUGGUGUCUUUUGCAUGUUCUUGGACAAAUGUGUGCUACCUGCCCAGGCGCCUGCAACCAUUGAGCCCACAUGUGCCCCACGUGUGCCCUGCGGGUGGUCCCGGGCCUGGCCAGGGCUCAGUGCUCCUCUUCCCCCUCCUCCCUGUUCCCACCCCUCAUGAAGCACACUGCGUGUCCAUCCCAUGUACCCGUGGGUCGACACACGCUCUUGCCACGCCCUGAGCGUGUACACAUGAUGUGUUCUAUGCAUUCACCCUGCCCCCCAGCCCGCCCUGCAGAGGACAAGAUGGGUGGCCCCGGCUCCCUUUCCCCUAACCGCCCCUGCCCGCUGUGCAGCCGUGUGCGUUGGCGUGUGUUUCUGUGUCACUGGCGUGUCACGUGAUGUAGCCGUGUUUGCUGACAUGAGCCCCUGCCCCCUUCUCUGUUUCUCCGUUGGUUUCUAGAGCUCUCUCCCUCCCCUUCUCAGAGGGGACAGGACUCCUGGGGCCUGGCUGGGGCCCAGAGCCAGGCCGCCCUCUCCUGUUAGCCCUCAGAGUCCCAUUUCUGUUAGCCCUCAGAGUCCCAUUUCUAUUGGUGACCAACUUGCAAAUGGAUAAAACACAGGAAAAUCCUGCCCCCCCCUUCCUCCCUGCAUGUCCUGUCCCCAGAGCCCCCCACCCCACCCUGGGCCAGGUCAGGCCCUGUGGGACGGGAGAAAUAGCAACCAAUCCAACAGCGGG